GGCCGAGGGCGGGCGGCUCCGGGGAGGGAUCCUGGAGGACCCCCGGGCUGCUGCGUCCGCGGUGGGCAGGGGCGCCCCUGGUGAGGGAGCGAUAAAGCGGGACGCAGGCACUGCGCUUCUCCCCUAAAACUGGAUAGUCACCACCUGUGGUUUUACCAACGGGGAGCAUUUUGAGAUAAAAGGAAAGGGUCCUGCGUAGCGACACGAAGUUACUGUUUGGAAAAGCUAUGUUUGUUUCUUUCUUUCUGCAGUGAUAGUCCCCGCCCCUUCCUUUAGCUCCACCUUUGUGACUUAGGAAAACUCAUGGGUGGCUGUGAGCACAAGAGUCAUCAGGCAGGCUCCAGACCUGUUAUUGAAAUAUAAACUGUUGGGUGUGUGCACAUCUUUAAAUUUUUGUAAACUUUGUGAAACGCAGUUGUAAAACCUGGUGCAGUUCUGUUUCGUGGCUAAGGAACGGGCGGAACCCAGGCCUGCAGCGAAGGCAGUAGCCCCGUGGUUGACCACAGUGGGCAUUGUCGCAGGCUGCUUCAGGGUGACGUGGGCGUUGUGACAGACUCCACAGCUCUCAGUAGCUGUGCUCUGACCCCAGAAGGGGAUAUGUUUCCGUAGCACCGAAGUGUCCAGCCAUGUUUGAAUCUACCCUUGUGUUCUGGGAUGGGCGGGCAAGUGGACACGCGUGUGCGCCUGGCUCUGGUAGUUUUGAUUGUGAGAACAGAAACUCCAGGGAGAGGUGGACACUCCAGCCCGCAGUGGGCCGGGCGUGAGCUCCCUCUGGGAAAGGUGCCGCUCCUUCUGGGGAUGCCACUCUCUUCCCUCCUCGGCAGCCGCGGCUCCUCGUCCCUUUGGCUUGCCCUGACCCUGUGUUUGUUGAGGAUCUUCUCUGCAUCUGGUUCCGCAAGAGUGAGGACUGGGACAGGAGUCUUCCCGUCACAGCCCCAGAACGUCCUGGCUCCGCUUCCUUUGGAGACAGAGCCUGGGUCCUUGACCCUCGGCACGGGCACUCACUCCUGCCCCCUGCGUGCUGGUGGGUGGGGCUGGGAGGUUCAGGGCCUUGCCUCCCAGAAAAUGCCUUCACGGCUUCCUCAGUGGGCACUGGCCGUACCUGGGAGGAUUGUGGAGGCAGAUCCCAAUGCUGGUGUAUUCCCUGGACAGAAAACCCCAGGAUGGAAGAUCCCUACUGAGGUUUCAUUCUGUUCCUCUGAUUGUACAGAAAGGGCUGCUUUGGCCUAGACAGGUGAGUAACUUGGUUAUGUGGCAAGUUAGUAUUGAAAUUCCAUGUUCAGUCAGUCUAGUGAAUAAAACCAACCCAGUGCAUCAGUCAGUCAGCCAGCCAGGUCAUGAGCUUGAUGACGGGUUCCCAGCAGUCAGUAGUGUUUACAGGGAGGUGCUGUUUGAGAUCUUGGGGUACCUCACAGGGCCCUUUGAGACACUGAUGUGAUAUCAUUUCUCCUCAGAUGGAGCGUCUGUGUGGCACCAGGUGUCCCUCUGGUUCCAGGAGGCUCAUCUCUCUGCCUCCAGUCCAUGGGCGGCAGAUUUCUUUGCUUUGGCUUUUUCCCAGUCACUCACAGGGAGGUAUUUAAAUCGCCACAGAAAGGGGAAGGUACCUAAAAUGAUCUGGGAGCCUGCAGUGACUGGUGAGAACUAACAGGCGGAGGCCGUGUGCGAGGGUUGAUGACGUCUGACAGACUGUACCUGUGCCUUUAGCGUGUCCACAGGAAGGGCAUCUGCAUUCACCAGCGCAGGGUGUGAGAGUGCCACAGAGAAGCAGAAAAACAUUGCUGAAUAAAAUGAAGAUCAUUCCAACAGCAACGGUAUUGCUGUCUUUAUUGCUUUGUAGAUUUUGGAAUGAGAAUCUCUGAGAAAUAGUAAUACAGUUAGAAUAGGCUGCAACCUAAGAUUAGUCCCCGAAUUUAUUGUUCUGUGAUGAGGGAGUAGAAGCCUCUGAAAUUCUAAAUGUGCUUCAGUCAGUGCACGAACGUCGUCACCUAAGGGUCCGGUCCUGGAAAUAAGGACAUUUCGUUUUCAUCCUGGUACCAAGAAUCUUGAUGAAUUGGUAAUUCUUUUAGAAUAGUUUUAUUAUUAACAAUUCUAAUAAUUAUUUAGAAUACUUUUAUUCUUCCCUGUUGACGCCUGCACUAUUUAAAGGAUGAUACUUUAAAAAAGAUAUUUGUGCCUAAAAUUUGGGGGGCUGUCACUUUGUCAGCCCAUUAAACGUGGGUAAGUUGCACUUCAAACGUUUUGCUUUGUUUUUCCCACUUUUCACCUAACAGAAAACCACUGGGCCUUGUUACUUGCUUGGUUUUGUUCGUCUGUGAUUUACCUUUGUCAUGGGUUUUUAGGUAUCUCCGAUCUAAUCUUUUAGAUAAAGGACUUUGAAGCACGUCUGCCUGGAAAUGGUUUGUAGGUUUCAGAAAUUUUGUGUGCAUUAUCAGAUUUGUCUCCAUUUUCAUGGUUUCUUUAAAGUUAGUUUUAAAGUGGGUUAUGUGAAAUCAUCUAGUAUCUGGGUACAGAGGAAUGGAUGAAUUCUCAGUUUUAUGUGUGUUUUAAAAGUGCACAAAUACAAAACGGAAAACAAGCGAUGUAAGUUGUCUCAGAAAAAAGUGCUUUUUAUAUUUUCAGGAGAAAGAGAAUGUAGAGAGAAUGGAACUGAUGAGUUUGAAGAGAUUCAGGUGAUAUUUCUUAAAGGAUAAAUGCACAUUUUAAAGGUUAUGAAGAGAUGGUCUUGGUAGGUUUUUAAAUAUACAUCUAGCAUCAUAUGUGCAAAAUUCCUUACAAUGUUAAGAGGAACUUGAGCUAAAACUUAACUCAUUUAAUAUUUGUAACAUUUUUGAAGUAGCGUUUAAAAGACAGUAAUUUCCCUACGGUGCUUUAAAUGGUGAAGAAUGCUGGUGUCGUACGAUUUUGAUGCAUUUUUUGUGCUGACUAUAGACUGGCGGGAAUGAUGCAGUUAGCGAGUUGAUACCCAGCAUCAUGUUGGCUUCUCCAGUUCACUGGUGGGCCUGCACCACAGCAGUUGGCUUCUCCAGUUCACUGGUGGGCCUGCACCGCAGCAGUUGGCUUCGUCAGUUCACUGGUGGGCCUGCACCGCAGCAGUUGGCUUCGCCAGUUCACUGGUGGGCCUGCACCGCAGCAGUUGGCUUCUCCAGUUCACUGGUGGGCCUGCACCGCAGCAGUUGGCUUCUCCAGUUCACUGGUGGGCCUGCACCGCAGCAGUUGGCUUCUCCAGUUCACUGGUGGGCCUGCACCGCAGCAGUUGACUUCUCCAGUUCACUGGUGGGCCUGCACCGCAGCAGUUGGCUUCGUCAGUUCACUGGUGGGCCUGCACCGCAGCAGUUGGCUUCUCCAGUUCACUGGUGGGCCUGCACCGCAGCAGUUGGCUUCGUCAGUUCACUGGUGGGCCUGCACCGCAGCAGUUGGCUUCUCCAGUUCACUGGUGGGCAUGCACCGCAGCAGUUGGCUUCGUCAGUUCACUGGUGGGCCUGCACCAGAGCAGUUGGCUUCUCCAGUUCACUGGUGGGCCUGCACCGCAGCAGUUGGCUUCGCCAGUUCACUGGUGGGCCUGCACCGCAGCAGUUGGCUUCGUCAGUUCACUGGUGGGCCUGCACCGGAGCAGUUGGCUUCUCCAGUUCACUGGUGGGCCUGCACCGCAGCAGUUGGCUUCGCCAGUUCACUGGUGGGCCUGCACCGCAGCAGUUGGCUUCGUCAGUUCACUGGUGGGCCUGCACCGGAGCAGUUGGCUUCUCCAGUUCACUGGUGGGCCUGCACCGCAGCAGUUGGCUUCUCCAGUUCACUGGUGGGCCUGCACCGCAGCAGUUGGCUUCUCCAGUUCACUGGUGGGCCUGCACCGCAGCAGUUGGCUUCGCCAGUUCACUGGUGGGCCUGCACCGCAGCAGUUGACUUCUCCAGUUCACUGGUGGGCAUGCACCGGAGCAGUUGGUUGGUUGUCCUGAGCAUACCACCAGGGGGUUAAAGUGUUUUCAGGCUGGAAGCAUUUGACACCAUGGCUCCCUGGGGUCUGUGGAGGUUCUGAGGCAAGGACUUUCCUUGCAGGUCUGUUUACCCAGCAGAGAGGGCAGUAGGGUCUGAAUGGUGUGGUGCACGUGGUGCCACGUGGUUUUGAGACGUGCUGGGAACUGGUUUUGUUGGAUGACUCGCUCUAGACCACAGUGGCAGUGUUGAAGCUUUCCAGCCACGGCUCUGUGGAUGUGUGCAGUGUUGGGAAUCAGGCUGGGCUGCCCUUGUUCCUUCUUUACAUUCCUCAGACGUUGUGCUUUACAGCCACAGUUUCAGUAACCGCUGCCAGAGCCCCACCUGUGCGUGUUCUCCAGGAUGGCUGCGUCUGGGCUCUGGGCGACUGAACCAGGUGCAGAGCGUCAGCCACAGCUGACGACUGCACUGCACUGGACUCCAGCCUGGGGCUCCCACCCCUGUGGCUGCACAGGAGACAAAACAACAACACUUGUUCCUUUGAAGCUGUUUGUUUUUUGUUUUGAGAUGAAGUUUCACUGUUGUCACCCAGGCUGGAGUGC